AAGGUGUCCGGCCACCUGCGCGCGCCGCCGGCUCCCCUCCAUUUCCCCCCGACUCCCGCCCCGGUCACCAUCCUACCCUCCUCCCUCCUCCUUUCCCCUUACUCCGCUCCCCUCUUUUCCCUCCCUCUCCUCCCCUUCCCUCUGUUCUCUCCUCCUCUUCCCCUCCCCUCCCCCGUCCGGAGCACUCUAUAUUCAAGCCACCGUUUCCUGCUUCACAAAAUGGCCACCGCACGCGACACCUACGGUCACGUGGCCUGCCGCCCUCUCAGUUUCGGGAAUCUGCCUAGCUCCCACUAAGGGGAGGCUACCCGCGGAAGAGCGAGGGCAGAUUAGACCGGAGAAAUCCCACCACAUCUCCAAGCCCGGGAACUGAGAGAGGAAGAAGAGUGAAGGCCAGUGUUAGGAAAAAAAAAACAAAAACAAAAAAAACGAAAAACGAAAGCUGAGUGCAUAGAGUUGGAAAGGGGAGCGAAUGCGUAAGGUUGGAAAGGGGGGCGAAGAGGCCUAGGUUAACAUUUUCAGGCGUCUUAGCCGGUGGAAAGCGGGAGACGCAAGUUCUCGCGAGAUCUCGAGAACUCCGAGGCUGAGACUAGGGUUUUAGCGGAGAGCACGGGAAGUGUAGCUCGAGAGAACUGGGACAGCAUUUCGCACCCUAAGCUCCAAGGCAGGACUGCUAGGGGCGACAGGACUAAGUAGGAAAUCCCUUGAGCUUAGACCUGAGGGAGCGCGCAGUAGCCGGGCAGAAGUCGCCGCGACAGGGAAUUGCGGUGUGAGAGGGAGGGCACACGUUGUACGUGCUGACGUAGCCGGCUUUCCAGCGGGUAUAUUAGAUCCGUGGCCGCGCGGUGCGCUCCAGAGCCGCAGUUCUCCCGUGAGAGGGCCUUCGCGGUGGAACAAACACUCGCUUAGCAGCGGAAGACUCCGAGUUCUCGGUACUCUUCAGGGAUGAGUCAUGUGGCAGUGGAAAAUGCGCUCGGGCUGGACCAGCAGUUUGCUGGCCUAGACCUGAACUCUUCAGAUAAUCAGAGUGGAGGAAGUACAGCCAGCAAAGGGCGCUAUAUUCCUCCUCAUUUAAGGAACCGAGAAGCUACUAAAGGUUUCUACGAUAAAGACAGUUCAGGGUGGAGUUCUAGCAAAGAUAAGGAUGCGUAUAGCAGUUUUGGAUCUCGUAGUGAUUCAAGAGGGAAGUCUAGCUUCUUCAGUGAUCGUGGAAGUGGAUCAAGGGGAAGGUUUGAUGAUCGUGGACGGAGUGAUUACGAUGGCAUUGGCAGCCGUGGUGACAGAAGUGGCUUUGGCAAAUUUGAACGUGGUGGAAACAGUCGCUGGUGUGACAAAUCAGAUGAAGAUGAUUGGUCAAAACCACUCCCACCAAGUGAACGCUUGGAACAGGAACUCUUUUCUGGAGGCAACACUGGGAUUAAUUUUGAGAAAUACGAUGACAUUCCAGUUGAGGCAACAGGCAACAACUGUCCUCCACAUAUUGAAAGUUUCAGUGAUGUUGAGAUGGGAGAAAUUAUCAUGGGAAACAUUGAGCUUACUCGUUAUACUCGCCCAACUCCAGUGCAAAAGCAUGCUAUUCCUAUUAUCAAAGAGAAAAGAGACUUGAUGGCUUGUGCCCAAACAGGGUCUGGAAAAACUGCAGCAUUUCUGUUGCCCAUCUUGAGUCAGAUUUAUUCAGAUGGUCCAGGCGAGGCUUUGAGGGCCAUGAAGGAAAAUGGAAGGUAUGGGCGCCGCAAACAAUACCCAAUCUCCUUGGUAUUAGCACCAACGAGAGAGUUGGCAGUACAGAUCUACGAGGAAGCCAGAAAAUUUUCAUACCGAUCUAGAGUUCGUCCUUGCGUGGUUUAUGGUGGUGCCGAUAUUGGUCAGCAGAUUCGAGACUUGGAACGUGGAUGCCAUUUGUUAGUAGCCACUCCAGGACGUCUAGUGGAUAUGAUGGAAAGAGGAAAGAUUGGAUUAGACUUUUGCAAAUACUUGGUGUUAGAUGAAGCUGAUCGGAUGUUGGAUAUGGGGUUUGAGCCUCAGAUUCGUAGAAUAGUCGAACAAGAUACUAUGCCUCCAAAGGGUGUCCGCCACACUAUGAUGUUUAGUGCUACUUUUCCUAAGGAAAUACAGAUGCUGGCUCGUGAUUUCUUAGAUGAAUAUAUCUUCUUGGCUGUAGGAAGAGUUGGCUCUACCUCUGAAAACAUCACACAGAAAGUAGUUUGGGUGGAAGAAUCAGACAAACGGUCAUUUCUGCUUGACCUCCUAAAUGCAACAGGCAAGGAUUCACUGACCUUAGUGUUUGUGGAGACCAAAAAGGGUGCAGAUUCUCUGGAGGAUUUCUUAUACCAUGAAGGAUACGCAUGUACCAGCAUCCAUGGAGACCGUUCUCAGAGGGAUAGAGAAGAGGCCCUUCACCAGUUCCGCUCAGGAAAAAGCCCAAUUUUAGUGGCUACAGCAGUAGCAGCAAGAGGACUGGACAUUUCAAAUGUGAAACAUGUUAUCAAUUUUGACUUGCCAAGUGAUAUUGAAGAAUAUGUACAUCGUAUUGGUCGUACGGGACGUGUAGGAAACCUUGGCCUGGCAACCUCAUUCUUUAACGAGAGGAACAUAAAUAUUACUAAGGAUUUGUUGGAUCUUCUUGUUGAAGCUAAACAAGAAGUGCCGUCUUGGUUAGAAAACAUGGCUUAUGAACACCACUACAAGGGUAGCAGUCGUGGACGUUCUAAGAGGUGGCUAUGGAGGCUUUUACAACAGUGAUGGAUAUGGAGGAAAUUAUAACUCCCAGGGGGUUGACUGGUGGGGUAACUGAGCCUGCUUUGCAGUAGGUCACCCUGCCAAACAAGCUAAUAUGGAAACCACAUGUAACUUAGCCAGACUAUACCUUGUGUAGCUUCAAGAACUCGCAGUACAUUACCAGCUGUGAUUCUCCACUGAAAUUUUUUUUUUAAGGGAGCUCAAGGUCACAAGAAGAAAUGAAAGGAACAAUCAGCAGCCCUGUUCAGAAGGUGGUUUGAAGACUUCAUUGCUGUAGUUUGGAUUAACUCCCCUCCCGCCUACCCCCAUCCCAAACUGCAUUUAUAAUUUUGUGACUGAGGAUCAUUUGUUUGUUAAUGUACUGUGCCUUUAACUUUAGACAACUUUUUAUUUUGAUGUCCUGUUGGCUCAGUAAUGCUCAAGAUAUCAAUUGUUUUGACAAAAUAAAUUUACUGAACUUGGGCUAAAAUCAAACCUUGGCACACAGGUGUGAUACAACUUAACAGGAAUCAUCGAUUCAUCCAUAAAUAAUAUAAGGAAAAACUUAUGCGGUAGCCUGCAUUAGGGCUUUUUGAUACUUGCAGAUUGGGGGAAAACAACAAAUGUCUUGAAGCAUAUUAAUGGAAUUAGUUUCUAAUGUGGCAAACUGUAUUAAGUUAAAGUUCUGAUUUGCUCACUCUAUCCUGGAUAGGUAUUUAGAACCUGAUAGUCUUUAAGCCAUUCCAGUCAUGAUGAGGUGAUGUAUGAAUACAUGCAUACAUUCAAAGCACUGUUUUCAAAGUUAAUGCAAGUAAAUACAGCAAUUCCUCUUUCAACGUUUAGGCAGAUCAUUAAUUAUGAGCUAGCCAAAUGUGGGCAUACUAUUACAGGGAAAGUUUAAAGGUCUGAUAACUUGAAAUAGGUUUUUAGGAGAAUUCAUCUACUUAGACUUUUUAAAUGCCUGCCAUAAAUGAAAUUGAAAUGGUAGAAUGGCUGACCACAGCAAUGACCAGCCCUCAUUAGGGCCCUGGAUGAUUUUUGGUCUAAUAACGCAUGCUAGUGUUGAUGUUUUUUGGUCAAGAGGGUAUGAACAGGAAGAAUUAAAUGCAGCAGGCUUUAUUUUAAAUGCCGAUUCACAUUACUCUGUUCAAGCUGCGUUGAGAUGUUAAACUGGCUUACUAUAGACUUCGUAAAAAUGGCUCCAGAAGAGUAACAAACUGAAAUCUUUGAGAUCACACAGGUUGGAAAUAUGUACAUAACUGCACAAGGUGUCAAUUCUGCUCUACAGUGCAGUUUUAGUCAGUUUUAGUUGCAUAGGUUUCCAUUGUAUUUAUAGUCUGUUUAUGCUAAAUCUGGCCAAAGAUGAGCAUUGUCCACCACUAAAAUGCCUCUGCCACUUUGAAUUCUGUGCUAAUUUUGUGGCCAGAAUGCGGUGAUCAAAACGCUCCAUCUUUUUACAGUGGCAUAGGAAGACGGCAAAAAUUUCCUAAAGUGCAAUAGAUUUUCAAGUGUAUUGUGCCUUGUUCUAAAACUUUUAUUAAGUAGGUGCACUUGACAGUAUUGAGGUCAUUUGUUAUGGUGCUAUUUCAAUUAGUCUAGGUUUAGGCCCUUGUACAUUUUGCCCAUAACUUUUUACAAAGUACUUCUUUUAUUGCACAUUCAGAGAAUUUUAUAUAUAUGUCUUGUGUGCGUGUCCUUAAACUUCCAAUCUUACUUUGUCUCUUGGAGAUUGUUGAACGCAGCUUGUCUAGGAAGGGGAUGGGACUAGAUUCUAAAAUUUAUUUGGGACCAUGGGAAUGAUAGUUGGGAAGAAAACUAUUUGCACACGACAGAUUUCUAGAUACUUUUUGCUGCUAGUUUUAUGUAAUAUUUAUUGAACAUUUUGACAAAUAUUUAUUUUUGUAAGCCUAAAAGUGAUUCUUUGAAAGUUUAAAGAAACUUGACCAAAAGACAGUACAAAAACACUGGCACUUGAAUGUUGAAUGUCACCGUAUGCGUGAAAUUAUAUAUUUCGGGGUAGUGUGAGCUUUUAAUGUUUAAGUCAUAUUAAACUCUUAAGUCAAAUUAAGCAGACCCGGCGUUGGCAGUGUAGCCAUAACUUUCUGAUGUUAGUAAAAACAAAAUUGGCGACUUGAAAUUAAAUCAUGCCAAGGUUUUGAUACACUUGUCUUAAGAUAUUAAUGAAACACUUCAAAACACUGAUGUGAAGUGUCCAGAUUCUCAGAUGUUUGUUGUGUGGAUUUUGUUUAGUUGUGUGUUUUUUUUUUUUUUUCAGUGAAUGUCUGGCACAUUGCAAUCCUCAAACAUGUGGUUAUCUUUGUUGUAUUGGCAUAAUCAGUGACUUGUACAUUCAGCAAUAGCAUUUGAGCAAGUUUUAUCAGCAAGCAAUAUUUUCAGUUAAUAAGGUUUCAAAAAUCAUGUAAGGAUUUAAACUUGCUGAAUGUAAAGAUUGAACCUCAAGUCACUGUAGCUUUAGUAAUUGCUUAUUGUAUUAGUUUAGAUGCUAGCACUGCAUGUGCUGUGCAUAUUCUGAUUUUAUUAAAAUAAAAAGUUGAACUGCACAGUCUCCUUUGUUGUUGUCAAUUGUGGUUUAUUUUCAGAGGUGUAAAUAAAGUGCUCUUGCCUGAAAAAUUGUAAAAUGUUAUUUUUUGCUUGUCAUCCAGUGCUAUUUUUUGAGAUGCCUCUUGGAUACAGAAUGACUCAUACCAUAAGUAUUUGCAAUGAAAGAUGAAGAUAGUAUUAGUUUGAAAUACAGUGAAACAGGAUUUUUGUAAUAGACGGAAAUCUAAAAGGCCCUUACUGAUAAUACAGCAUGUAUUAGAAAUUGGCUUAUACUUUGAACAAUUUGACAUGGGUGGGAGUCUCUUUGUUCUUUGAAGUAUCUAUUAUGAAGGAUGGUUGAACAGUGGAAGAAUGAGCAGGAUAAAAGUCAAGUGUGUCAGUAGUCCAACAAGUGAUGGUAAGUAUAUACUUAGGGAAGGAAUCAAGACUAUUUGGGCCAGGUGUGAUGAUUACAUAGUCCUAUAGUGCUAGUUUACUUGGAAGCUGAGGGGCAGGAAGAUUGCUUGAGCCCACGAGUUCAAGUCCAGCCUGGGCAACGUAUAGCAAGACCUUAUCUCUGAAAACAGGUAAUAAGACAUCUAUGCUUACUGUACACACUGCUGCAAUAGGCUGCUACCACAAGUGUAUAGGUGCUUGGUUAGAUUGAGCCAUACUAGCGGUUUGAUACGUUUCAAUCUAACAAAUACGUAUUCAGCUUUUGUUUCAGUAAGUUGAAGGUUUGCAGUAUGAUUAAGAAUUUUUUGCAUUGUAAGGAAGUAUGGUUCUGGAUAAUCUUUCCAGUCAUGAACUCAAAAUAAGCAUAAGUUUUUAGGGCAGAAUUUUGACACAUGGCCAUAUGUAUUUUGAAGAUAGAAAAGAUGAUGGUACUUGAGUCUCGAUUUAGUCAAAAUAAGCAUGGAAAGGUUUGGGAUUGCUAGAUUGGAUAGUCAAUGGCUGAAAGUGACUCAUGGAGUGAAACGAUGCUAAGGAGAGUUCAGUUUCCACUUUAUGUGAAUGAUGAGUGAACAUGACAAUCUGCUCUGGAGGAACUGCCAAAAUUUGAGGUUAUUUCUAGUCUAGCAUGGUUAGGAUUAUGGUGACAUAAAUUUAGUAUGUUUACAUACUACAUUAAUGUGGUUUAAUUUUAAUUACACUUAAAUGCAGUUGUCACUCUUGGGCACUGUUGAUGUGUUUCCUGGAUUCUUGGCUGAAUUUCAAGAUUUUUAAAAUGGCUUUAUAGGAGCUGUGUCUAACCUUCAUGCUUAAAAUGUUUCCUUUGCUCCUAUGCUCUACGUGACCUGCUUGAGUGGCCACAGGCUUGCUCUUUAGAGCACAGUGACUUUGUUGAUAGGGCCUCACUACUCCCACAAUGCAGAGAUACCUACUUAUUGUAGGUACAGGGCAUUGAAAGUUAUAAGACUAUCUUUGGGUUUUGCUUUCUUGUGUUCCAUUCUAUUUUUAAUACAAUUCUGAGUAUAUUUAAA